CAAACAAAAGAAAAAGACUGGGGUGAUGCUGCCUCGAGUUGUCCUGACUCCUCUGAAGGUAAACGGGGCCCACGUGGAAUCUGCAUCAGGUAUGUGUAAACUCAUGGUUGUGAUGCUUUUUCCUCAGGUCCUGGGGACCUGGCCUCCCUCUGUCAGCAGUUUCUGACCUAAUAGUGCGAUACUAGGAGAGCUGUCGGGCCACAGGCAAGAGCCCUGCCAAUGGAUGAGGCCUGCCAUAGGUUCUAGUGCUGGGCUCUGCUGUGUGCCUUCCUCUUUGUCUCCCAGGGCAGUCGUGAGGAUCCAACGGAGGAUUUGAUUAUGCCAGUGCUUUGUAAAAGGUGUAGUGCUAUACAAAUAAAGAUGGCAGUUUGGCACCUGUAAGGUGAUAUUUUAAAGCCAGACCAUGAAGUGGUGGUUUCUCUCAGCCUAAGGCUGGGAGAUGGAAGCAUCCCAGUAUUGCUGGCAGCAUCUCAGGGAGAGCUGGGAGAAAUGAGCUUGUCUGAGAGCCAUGGGCGCGGCUUGGUGAUACUUUUGACCAGUGGAAUGCUGUGCCUUCAGGGUUCUCGGGCUGCCACGCCGAUGGCGAGAGCGGCAGCCCGUCCAGCAGCAGCAGCGGCUCUCUGGCCCUGGGCAGCGCUGCUAUUCGUGGCCAGGCCGAGGUCACCCAGGACCCUGCCCCGCUCCUGAGAGGCUUCCGGAAGCCAGCCACAGGUGAGUGGCGUGGCACUUAUUUCUCUGCCUGUAAAGGGGGCCCCUGCAGGCCUAGUGAGAAGAUGAUGUCUUCUAUUCCAAUUCCUUUACCAGUUUAUUUUUACUUCUUGGGUGGCCCUCUAUUUUUUGUUUAUUUUUACUUUGUAAUUUGCUUAUUUCAUUUGUAGCUCUCUGCUAAACUGUGAGAACUCCUUUCAGGCAGAGAUGAUGCCAUACUGUUUCUCGUAUGUCCCUGUAGGCCUAGUCUAUGCCUGCCUUGUACUGCAUAGUAAGUGUUUGAGUGAGUGAAAACUGCUUCUGAGCUUCUCAGUGAAGAAUUCCAACACCCCUUUUCUCUCUUCGGUAGCAUGUUGCCACAUUUGUUCCCAACAUCUGUAGUCUGUAUCAGACGCUCCCUUUUUUACAACCUAGUCAGUAUGUUGAGUGGAAGCAUGUGUUGAAUUUUGGGGAUGCAAACAAAUUCAGUAGUGCUAUUAUCUAUACCUCCCACCCCUCACCCCACCCCACCCCCAUUAGGGUUAUUUGCAAUAUUAGUAUGCUCUUUGCUAUUUCAGGAUUUAAUUCUUAAUGACCCACAUGCUGGUUUUUUUUGUAGAUGAAACCAUUAAGAAGACAAGCUUUUGCUUCUGAGAAUUAGAGUAAACCUUUGCCCAUGUGAGAACUAGGUUUGCUGUCUUGCUGCUUUUCCAGCUCAUCAGCAGUGCUCAAUCUAAGGUCUCACAGGUCUCUAGUCCUAGUGAGUUUUUCAGAUAAAAGUAACAUUUGCUGAGGCUUCUGUGAGAGGUAUUAGCAUCUCAGUUGGCUUUGAACAGUCCUUAGUACAUUUCUGCAUGGAGAUCAUCCCUCUCCAGCCCAUUCACAGAAGGCUUCUGCAGAUUUUUCUAUAGUAUACUAACUAGAUUUACUUUUAGAUAAUUCUCAUGAUUUCUCCAGUUGAGCUUUGUGGAGCCUGUUCUCCAGCUUUGGAGGGAAGCUCAGAACCUGCCCCUUGCCUGAUUUUCUGUGGGAAGUGUCCUUUUCAGGCUGUGACACAGCACGGUACAGAGUUUUGUCUGAGGAGAUGCAACCCCAAGUGUUCUCCUGGGUUUGAUGGCAAUGACAGUAACCUGGAAAGAAUAUACAGGUCAAAUGAAGCGCAACAGAGGGGAAGAAAUAGAUUUUGAGACACCUGGGUCCAUUCUUGUCAACACCAACCUCCGUGCCCUGAUCAACUCUCGGACCUUCCAUGCCUUACCAUCACACUUCCAGCAGCAGCUCCUCUUCCUCCUGCCUGAAGUAGACAGACAGGUGGGGACGGAUGGCCUGUUGCGUCUCAGCAGCAGUGCACUAAAUAACGAGUUUUUUACCCAUGCGGCUCAGAGCUGGCGGGAGCGCCUGGCUGAUGGUGAAUUUACUCAUGAGAUGCAAGUCAGGAUACGACAGGAAAUGGAGAAGGAAAAGAAGGUGGAACAAUGGAAAGAAAAGUUCUUUGAAGACUACUAUGGACAGAAGCUGGGUUUGACCAAAGAAGAGUCAUUGCAGCAGAACGUGGGCCAGGAGGAGGCUGAAAUCAAAAGUGGCUUGUGUGUCCCAGGAGAAUCAGUGCGUAUACAGCGUGGUCCAGCCACCCGACAGCGAGAUGGGCAUUUUAAGAAACGCUCUCGGCCAGAUCUCCGAACCAGAGCCAGAAGGAAUCUGUACAAAAAACAGGAGUCAGAACAAGCAGGGGUUGCUAAGGAUGCAAAAUCUGUGGCCUCAGAUGUUCCCCUCUACAAGGAUGGGGAGGCUAAGACUGACCCAGCAGGGCUGAGCAGUCCCCAUCUGCCAGGCACAUCCUCUGCAGCACCCGACCUGGAGGGUCCCGAAUUCCCAGUUGAGUCUGUGGCUUCUCGGAUCCAGGCUGAGCCAGACAACUUGGCACGUGCCUCUGCAUCUCCAGACAGAAUUCCUAGCCUGCCUCAGGAAACUGUGGAUCAGGAACCCAAGGAUCAGAAGAGGAAAUCCUUUGAGCAGGCGGCCUCUGCAUCCUUUCCCGAAAAGAAGCCCCGGCUUGAAGAUCGUCAGUCCUUUCGUAACACAAUUGAAAGUGUUCACACCGAAAAGCCACAGCCCACUAAAGAGGAGCCCAAAGUCCCGCCCAUCCGGAUUCAACUUUCACGUAUCAAACCACCCUGGGUGGUUAAAGGUCAGCCCACUUACCAGAUAUGCCCCCGGAUCAUCCCCACCACGGAGUCCUCCUGCCGGGGUUGGACUGGCGCCAGGACCCUCGCAGACAUUAAAGCCCGUGCUCUGCAGGUCCGAGGGGCGAGAGGUCACCACUGCCAUAGAGAGGCGGCCACCACUGCCAUCGGAGGGGGGGGUGGCCCGGGUGGAGGUGGCGGCGGGGCCACCGAUGAGGGAGGUGGCAGAGGCAGCAGCAGUGGUGAUGGUGGUGAGGCCUGUGGCCACCCUGAGCCCAGGGGAGGCCCGAGCACCCCUGGAAAGUGUACGUCAGAUCUACAGCGAACACAACUACUGCCGCCUUAUCCUCUAAAUGGGGAGCAUACCCAGGCCGGAACUGCCAUGUCCAGAGCUAGGAGAGAGGACCUGCCUUCUCUGAGAAAGGAGGAAAGCUGCCUACUACAGAGGGCUACAGUUGGACUCACAGAUGGGCUAGGAGAUGCCUCCCAACUCCCCGUUGCUCCCACUGGGGACCAGCCAUGCCAGGCCUUGCCCCUACUGUCCUCCCAAACCUCAGUAGCUGAGAGAUUAGUGGAGCAGCCUCAGUUGCAUCCGGAUGUUAGAACUGAAUGUGAGUCUGGCACCACUUCCUGGGAAAGUGAUGAUGAGGAGCAAGGACCCACCGUUCCUGCAGACAAUGGUCCCAUUCCGUCUCUAGUGGGAGAUGAUACAUUAGAGAAAGGAACUGGCCAAGCUCUUGACAGUCAUCCCACUAUGAAGGAUCCUGUAAAUGUGACCCCCAGUUCCACACCUGAAUCCUCACCGACUGAUUGCCUGCAGAACAGAGCAUUUGAUGACGAAUUAGGGCUUGGUGGCUCAUGCCCUCCUAUGAGGGAAAGUGAUACUAGACAAGAAAACUUGAAAACCAAGGCUCUCGUUUCUAACAGUUCUUUGCAUUGGAUACCCAUCCCAUCGAAUGAUGAGGUAGUGAAACAGCCCAAACCAGAAUCCAGAGAACACAUACCAUCUGUUGAGCCCCAGGUUGGAGAGGAGUGGGAGAAAGCUGCUCCCACCCCUCCUGCAUUGCCUGGGGAUUUGACAGCUGAGGAGGGUCUAGAUCCUCUUGACAGCCUUACUUCACUCUGGACUGUGCCAUCUCGAGGAGGCAGUGACAGCAAUGGCAGUUACUGUCAACAGGUGGACAUUGAAAAGCUGAAAAUCAACGGAGACUCUGAAGCACUGAGUCCUCACGGUGAGUCCACGGAUACAGCCUCUGACUUUGAAGGUCACCUCACGGAGGACAGCAGUGAGGCUGACACUAGAGAAGCUGCAGUGACAAAGGGAUCUUCGGUGGACAAGGAUGAGAAACCCAAUUGGAACCAAUCUGCCCCACUGUCCAAGGUGAAUGGUGACAUGCGUCUGGUUACAAGGACAGAUGGGAUGGUUGCUCCUCAGAGCUGGGUGUCUCGAGUAUGUGCGGUCCGCCAAAAGAUCCCAGAUUCCCUACUGCUGGCCAGUACUGAGUACCAGCCAAGAGCCGUGUGCCUGUCCAUGCCUGGGUCCUCAGUGGAGGCCACUAACCCACUUGUGAUGCAGUUGCUGCAGGGUAGCUUGCCCCUAGAGAAGGUUCUUCCACCAGCCCACGAUGACAGCAUGUCAGAAUCCCCACAAGUACCACUUACAAAAGACCAGAGCCAUGGCUCGCUACGCAUGGGAUCUUUACAUGGUCUUGGAAAAAACAGUGGCAUGGUUGAUGGAAGCAGCCCCAGUUCUUUAAGGGCUUUGAAGGAGCCUCUUCUGCCAGAUAGCUGUGAAACAGGCACUGGUCUUGCCAGGAUUGAGGCCACCCAGGCUCCUGGAGCACCCCAAAAGAAUUGCAAGGCAGUCCCAAGUUUUGACUCCCUCCAUCCAGUGACAAAUCCCAUUACAUCCUCUAGGAAACUGGAAGAAAUGGAUUCCAAAGAGCAGUUCUCUUCCUUUAGUUGUGAAGAUCAGAAGGAAGUCCGUGCUAUGUCACAGGACAGUAAUUCAAAUGCUGCUCCAGGAAAGAGCCCAGGAGAUCUUACUACCUCGAGAACACCUCGUUUCUCAUCUCCAAAUGUGAUCUCCUUUGGUCCAGAGCAGACAGGUCGGGCCCUGGGUGAUCAGAGCAAUGUUACAGGCCAAGGGAAGAAGCUUUUUGGCUCUGGGAAUGUGGCUGCAACCCUUCAGCGCCCCAGGCCUGCGGACCCGAUGCCUCUUCCUGCUGAGAUCCCUCCAGUUUUUCCCAGUGGGAAGUUGGGACCAAGCACAAACUCCAUGUCUGGUGGGGUACAGACUCCAAGGGAAGACUGGGCUCCAAAGCCACAUGCCUUUGUUGGCAGCGUCAAGAAUGAGAAGACUUUUGUGGGGGGUCCUCUUAAGGCAAAUGCCGAGAACAGGAAAGCUACUGGGCAUAGUCCCCUGGAACUGGUGGGUCACUUGGAAGGGAUGCCCUUUGUCAUGGACUUGCCCUUCUGGAAAUUACCCCGAGAGCCAGGGAAGGGGCUCAGUGAGCCUCUGGAGCCUUCUUCUCUCCCCUCCCAACUCAGCAUCAAGCAGGCAUUUUAUGGGAAGCUUUCUAAACUCCAACUGAGUUCCACCAGCUUUAAUUAUUCCUCUAGCUCUCCCACCUUUCCCAAAGGCCUUGCUGGAAGUGUGGUGCAGCUGAGCCACAAAGCAAACUUUGGUGCGAGCCACAGUGCAUCACUUUCCUUGCAAAUGUUCACUGACAGCAGCACGGUGGAAAGCAUCUCGCUCCAGUGUGCGUGCAGCCUGAAAGCCAUGAUCAUGUGCCAAGGCUGCGGUGCGUUCUGUCACGAUGACUGUAUUGGACCCUCAAAGCUCUGUGUAUUGUGCCUUGUGGUGAGAUAAUAAAUUAUGGCCAUGGGAAACAUUGUAUAUUUAGUGUGUGUAUUUUGAUAAUGAUUGAUCUUAAAUCUGUAUACAGAAUAUCAUUGAUAUAAUACUCUUUAGGCAGGAGCACUCUUGCCUUCCCCCAAAAUUUACACUGCUAAAGCCCUCUGUCACUUGGCGACCCUUCUGGUCUUGCUGGAGGGGUUUCCUGGGUAUAACCCAUUGGGCUGCCCAAGGCCAGCCAGCCUGAGCUCUCCUGCAAGACAGAGCCUGAUGUGGCACGGAGUGGGGUUGCGGGGGGUGGGGGGACUGCCUGACUCCCAGAGGGACUUGAAACUGAAGCAAGAAGGUUGCAUUCUCCACCAAGGGAGUUAACCUACCUGAACUAAGUAGAAAUGCCAGUCUUCCACUACCCCCUCCCUGCCAUCUUUUCUUCUGCUACUUUGGGGAGUUGAUGGCCAGGAAAGAAGCCAGCACAGGGUUAAAGUAACUCCUGGCAUUGCCCACCAGGGGGCUGGUGCACCUGCUGACCUCAGGGUCACAGUUGAGUCAUUUGCCAGUUGACGGAGCAAGUUUGACCUUGGUUCUGUUGCUGAAGCAAAUUUGGAACUUUUCUGUCUCAGUGUGAUCCACUAACCCACAGGAUCAUUUGGAACCUUGAAUAGCUCUGCUUGGACAAUGGGGUUGGGGAAUAGGGUUGUCUUUCCUAUGAAAAUGCCAUCUGUAGACCUUGUGAGUCAGCCGUCCAGAUGUUUGCAGGUGAAUUCCUCUGCUUGACAUCCUCCCUGUCACUUUGGACCCUAUGGGAGUGGGCAUCUCCACGCACCUGUGUAUGUGAAAGUCAUUUUACAUUUCAAAGCAGUGUGUGUUUCUUAUUUUUAUAUUUUUAACUCUUUAUUCUUGGAUGUAUAAAGUGAACUUUUUGGCUUCUGUAAGUAUGCUCUAUGCACCUCUAAUGUUUUAUCAUGUAUUUAUAUGUUGUACACAGUACUGGCUGAUUCUGUAAAUGGAUGUAUUGUACAGAGAACAUGAACGUCUCUUCCUAAUUUUACAUCUUCAGCAUCAUUGCAUUAAAGUGGUGUAAUCUCCUUCUCUACAUCUGUUGUCAGAGCCACUGAGUGCUGUGCUGCUCGACGUGAGGGUGAAAUGAUUGACUUGUGACCUGCCAGGUUGCCCGAUGCCCUGUUGGGUCACCGGCUGGACCUGCUGCAGCCUGCAGAGCCACAGUCAGCCUGCCCACAUGCCACCGAGCAAACGCAUCUUGCUUUUCACAUCUCUCCUCCUACAGCCUUAAUGGCUGCUUGCUGCCAUAUGUGACAAAUCACCACCACCAGUGUUAAGUGCUUCUGGAUUCAUGGGUGAGUUCCCUGGGCAGCCCCCAGGAAGGCCUUCCAGAUCUGGCUCCAGGGUCACCACCUGUCACAGCAAUACCUGGGACCAUGCUCUCCUGGGACUGUGAGGCUCCUUUUGACGUACUUUUGACAUCAGGCAGGUUUGGGAAGAAACAAAGCCAUGCCUGCUCCUGCCUCUCUCCCAACAUGUUUCCAGCAAGUAGAUGCCCCUGUGUGUGUUUUCCCUUGCCUUGUUUCCUGCCUUAUAUCUUGUAUUUCGACUUAUUACAGAGUUGAGGGUUCUUGCUUAAUUUAGAUCAAGUAUAAAAUUUGUAUGACUUCAAGUCUCAUUUUAUCUGAAAGGUUUUUUUCUCAUUUAAUCUGAUGUGGCAUUUUCGUCAUCUGAAGCAUGAGUGACAAGUUGGGAAUGAUGUGGUGAUUUAGAAUGCAGUAUUGGCCAAGUCCAAGUUGUCAACUUAAGCGUCUGUUUACCAAAGACCGGGAACAGGGGCCCAAACAUGUCCAGUCCUCUUCUUCCCUCUGCUGGAACCUUUGGGGACACUCAAGGGUACAGUUUGACACUGAUCUGGUCCAUGAGGCUGCCCAGAGAAAGCACUGCUUCUGUAUGUCUCUUGUGGUAUUGGAACAAUAAACCCGUACAACCUGCA